AGAGCCGAGACAAGGCAGUUGGAGGCAGCGGUGGCAGGGGCUGCAGGAGCAAGUGACCAGGAGCAGGACUGGGGACAGAUCAUCACGCCUGGGAGUUGCGGGAGCGGGUGCGCUGCCUCGGAGUCCCGCGUGUAUACGGCUCCCCAGCCGUCUGCCCCUGCCUGAUCGCCCCUGCACGAACCAGACCCUUCGCCGCCCUCACGAUGACUACCUCUCCGAUCCUGCAGCUGCUGCUGCGGCUCUCACUGUGCGGGCUGCUGCUCCAGAGGGCGGAGACAGGCUCUAAGGGGCAGACGGCGGGGGAGCUGUACCAGCGCUGGGAACGGUACCGCAGGGAGUGCCAGGAGACCUUGGCAGCCGCGGAACCGCCUUCAGGCCUCGCCUGUAACGGGUCCUUCGAUAUGUACGUCUGCUGGGACUAUGCUGCACCCAAUGCCACUGCCCGUGCGUCCUGCCCCUGGUACCUGCCCUGGCACCACCAUGUGGCUGCAGGUUUCGUCCUCCGCCAGUGUGGCAGUGAUGGCCAAUGGGGACUUUGGAGAGACCAUACACAAUGUGAGAACCCAGAGAAGAAUGAGGCCUUUCUGGACCAAAGGCUCAUCUUGGAGCGGUUGCAGGUCAUGUACACUGUCGGCUACUCCCUGUCUCUCGCCACACUGCUGCUAGCCCUGCUCAUCUUGAGUUUGUUCAGGCGGCUACAUUGCACUAGAAACUAUAUCCACAUCAACCUGUUCACGUCUUUCAUGCUGCGAGCUGCGGCCAUUCUCAGCCGAGACCGUCUGCUACCUCGACCUGGCCCCUACCUUGGGGACCAGGCCCUUGCGCUGUGGAACCAGGCCCUCGCUGCCUGCCGCACGGCCCAGAUCGUGACCCAGUACUGCGUGGGUGCCAACUACACGUGGCUGCUGGUGGAGGGCGUCUACCUGCACAGUCUCCUGGUGCUCGUGGGAGGCUCCGAGGAGGGCCACUUCCGCUACUACCUGCUCCUCGGCUGGGGGGCCCCCGCGCUUUUCGUCAUUCCCUGGGUGAUCGUCAGGUACCUGUACGAGAACACGCAGUGCUGGGAGCGCAACGAAGUCAAGGCCAUUUGGUGGAUUAUACGGACCCCCAUCCUCAUGACCAUCUUGGUAGGAUCGGUCCCGCCUCCACCAGGCCGCCCUCAGGGAUUUCCCAUUCUGGGAAGUGGGCUGCCACCUCCUCCUGCCCCUUCAGAAUGGGAUCGCGGCUGGCUCAGCCCUUAUCUCUCCCCACAGAUUAAUUUCCUCAUUUUUAUCCGCAUUCUUGGCAUUCUCCUGUCCAAGCUGAGGACACGGCAAAUGCGCUGCCGGGAUUACCGGCUGAGGCUGGCUCGCUCCACGCUGACGCUGGUGCCCCUGCUGGGUGUCCACGAGGUGGUGUUUGCUCCCGUGACAGAGGAACAGGCCCGGGGCGCCCUGCGCUUCGCCAAGCUCGGCUUUGAGAUCUUCCUCAGCUCCUUCCAGGGCUUCCUGGUCAGCGUCCUCUACUGCUUCAUCAACAAGGAGGUGCAGUCGGAGAUCCGCCGUGGCUGGCACCACUGCCGCCUGCGCCGCAGCCUGGGCGAGGAGCAACGCCAGCUCCCGGAGCGCGCCUUCCGGGCCCUGCCCUCCGGCUCCGGCCCGGGCGAGGUCCCCACCAGCCGCGGCUUGUCCUCGGGGACCCUCCCAGGGCCUGGGAAUGAGGCCAGCCGGGAGUUGGAAAGUUACUGCUAGGGGGCGGGAUCCCCGUGUCUGUUCAGUUAGCAUGGAUUUAUUGAGUGCCAACUGCGUGCCAGGCCCAGUACGGAGGACGCUGGGGAAAUGGUGAAGGAAACAGAAAAAAGGUCCCUGCCCUUCUGGAGAUGACAACUGAGUGGGGAAAACAGACCGUGAACACAAAACAUCAAGUUCCACACACGCUAUGGAAUGGUUAUGAAGGGAAGCGAGAAGGGGGCCUAGGGUGGUCUGGGAGGCGUCUCCAAGGAGGUGACACUUAAGCCAUCCCCGAAAGAGGUGAAAGAGAUCACUUUGGGGAGAGCUGGAGAACAGGAUUCUAGGCGGAAGCGAUAGCAUAGGCAAAGGCCCUUGGGCAGGAAGGCGCUCAGCCUUGGCUGGAGUAGAAUUAAGUCAGAGCCAACAGGUGGGGAGAGACAGAGAAGUGGGCAGGGGCACCCAAGUUGGGAUUUCAUUUCAGGUGCAUUGGAGAUUCUUAGGAGUGUCUCUUGGGGGUAAUAUUUUAUUUUUUAAAAAAUGAGGAUGUCACUCUUACCCAGGUUGGUCUUGAACUCCUGGGCUCAAGCAAUCCUCCCACCACGGGUCUCUCAAAGUGCUGGGAUUACAGGCGUGAGCCACCGCACCCGGCUUUUUUUUUUUUUUUUAAACGGAGUCUCACUCUGUCACCCAGGCUGGAGUGCAGUGGUGCAAUUUCAGCUCACUGCACCCUCCACCUCCCGAGUUCAAGCCUCCCGGGUAGCUGGGAUUACAGGCACCGCCACCAUGCCUGGCUAAUUUUUGCAUUUUCAGUAGAGAUAGGGUUUCUCCAUGUUGGCCAGGCUGGUCUCGAACUCCUGACCUCAAGUGAUCCACCCACCUCAGCCUCCCAAAGUGCUGGGAUUACAGGCAUAAGCCACCAUGCCCGGCCCAAAUGGGCUAAUGUUUUAAACAGAUCCUUCUUGUCUGCCCUGUAGGAGGACAAAUUAUCAGGGGCAGGGGUGGAAGCUGGAGCCCAGAAAGGAGGGGACUGCAGGUGGGAAGUGAUGGUGGCUGGACCAGGAUGGAGGCCACUGAGGGGUAUGAAGCAGUCGGAUUUGAAGCUGUUUAAAAGGUGGAGGUGAGAGGAUUUCAUGAAGGAGCACAUGAGGACACAGCAGCAGAGAGGACUCCUUGGCUUUGGAUGGUGGAGAGACUAAAGAUAGAGAGAUUGGGUUCGGGUAGGGGGAGAACCACGUGUGCUCUUUGGAAAGGUUAGGCUGGCAGUGUUUGUAGGACAUGACAGGACACUGAGUGUAAGGGUCUGGAGCUCUCAGGAGAGGGGCGAGCUGGAGAUAGUAAUGUGAGAGGCACUGGGUCCUGAGAGGGUGAUUUGGUGUGGACCGGAGCACAGGUGAGGCAAGGCAGGCCUCGCAGCUGAAACUUUAUAUCCAGAGCAGCCAGGGCCACUGCUGGCUGCGGAGUGAGGACGCAUAUCCCCACUGUCCUUAGAUGGGUGGCCCCUGGAACCUGGGAGAAUGAGGGGGCAUGCUGACAGUCUCAUUGUGGCUGGACCACCUGUACAUACACCCACAAGACCCUCACCCCUAAAUCCUCCCCCUACACAUAUGCACACUUAAGUUACCGUAUGGGUGUUGUCGAGCAUUUUCCCUGGGGUCUGUGGCUCCCUGGACCGACAUGCCCCAAAGCUGAACUCAGCCUUUUCAAGCUUGCGGCCCUGCUGCCCAAUUCCCCUACACCCUGCCUUGUGGGUUCUCGCGGGGUGGGGGCCUUAGGGCAAGGCUCUUGUAAAUAAAGUAUAAGAAACAGUU